CCUGGUAAAUCUUGUAGUCAAAUCAAUUGCUGCAGCUGAGCAAAGAGAGCCGCGGUCCCUCCUUCCCUGGGAGAAGCGGAUGUUAUCCCAGCACCUUCUGCAAGCUGGUCAGGGACCGAGUCCCGGAAACUUGGGUCUAGCAUGUGUCUCUGAGCCUAGAUUUGGUUUCCAGUUGUGUAGCACUUGGCUGAAGACCAACAAAGGGGCCGAGCCAACUAUAGAAAGUCAUCUCUUUAAGCAGUUUUCAAGAUUGAACCUAUACCAUUUUUAUAAUAAGAAAAAAAAAUGUACUCCCCAGACAACAAUGGAUGUGAAGCAAUUGCCAGUCUUCAGCCUGUGAGACAAAGGGGGACUAAGAGCAUGUUUACUUGCUUGGAAGGUGCUCAGCUGCUGUUUUAUGACCAGCUUCCCUGGAAAAGCCUGACCAACAGAGUGGUCAUAGGCCCAGCUGAACACCGGUCAACAAAAAUGUCCUGCCCAUGUCUGGUGUUAGGCCAAUGGAAGGAAACCUCCAAAGAGGCUGGUGUGAACAGGACAAGACUGAAGAAAAGAAGAGACAGGAGGCCACUUUAGUAGUCCAGGUGACAGCUACAGUAAUGGAGAUGGGCCAACCAGGUUGGUGCCAGCUAUAUUUAUGUCUUCUCAGAGUCAUAACAUUCCAGACUUAGAAGGACAGAGACGUUUAGUUGGAUACAUGACAGAAAGUCUAUAGCAUAAAAAAUAGACGCAUUUCUAGGCUAUAGCCUACACGUUGCAUAAAUGAUGAAAGUUUCCUGUGAAGCAUAACAAUCCCUGAUUGUGAAAGUACCCCACAAGCAUCGUUAACUAUAAAGUAAGGAAAAGUAUGAAAGAACCAUCUGGUUGAGUCUAAAGUUGGAAGAUCACCAUAUCCACCAGAAGACCCAGGAUGGAUCUGCAACAAAGCACCACCAUCACUUCCCUAGAGAAAUGGUGUUUGGAUGAGUCACUGUCUGGCUGCAGAAGACAUUAUAGUGUCAAGAAAAAACUGAAGUUAAUUCGAGUCUUAGGCCUUUUCAUGGGUCUGGUAGCCAUUAGCACUGUCUCAUUUUCAAUCAGUGCCUUUUCUGAGACAGAUACACAGAGCACAGGAGAGGCCAGUGUUGUAAGUGGCCCUAGGGUAGCACAGGGUUACCAUCAGAGAACUCUCUUAGAUUUAAAUGACAAGAUUCUGGAUUAUACUCCACAGCCACCUCUUUCUAAGGAAGGCGAGUCUGAGAAUAGUACAGAUCACGCCCAAGGAGACUACCCGAAAGACAUCUUUUCCCUUGAGGAGAGAAGAAAAGGUGCGAUCAUUCUGCAUGUCAUUGGAAUGAUCUACAUGUUCAUAGCCUUAGCCAUUGUCUGUGAUGAGUUCUUUGUUCCUUCUUUGACUGUCAUCACUGAAAAACUGGGCAUCUCUGAUGAUGUGGCUGGAGCCACCUUCAUGGCUGCAGGAGGGUCAGCCCCAGAACUUUUCACAUCUCUCAUAGGGGUAUUUAUCGCUCACAGCAACGUUGGCAUAGGCACAAUUGUAGGUUCAGCAGUAUUCAACAUCCUCUUUGUUAUUGGCAUGUGUGCUCUGUUUUCUAGAGAAAUCUUAAACCUGACAUGGUGGCCGCUCUUUCGAGAUGUGUCUUUCUACAUUGUUGACUUGAUCAUGCUGAUCAUAUUUUUCCUGGAUAAUGUCAUCAUGUGGUGGGAAAGCUUGCUUCUCUUAACAGCUUAUUUUUGCUAUGUGGUUUUCAUGAAAUUCAACGUCCAAGUAGAAAAAUGGGUGAAGCAAAUGAUAAACCGCAAUAAGGUCGUCAAGGUGACAGCACCAGAAGCCCAAGCAAAGCCAUCUGCAGCCAGGGACAAGGAUGAACCAACUCUACCGGCUAAGCCGCGUCUCCAGCGAGGUGGAAGCUCUGCCUCCCUCCACAACAGUCUCAUGAGGAAUAGCAUCUUCCAACUCAUGAUACACACCCUUGACCCACUCGCCGAAGAACUUGGAUCAUAUGGAAAACUAAAAUAUUAUGACACAAUGACUGAAGAAGGGAGGUUCAGAGAAAAGGCUUCAAUUCUCCACAAGAUCGCCAAGAAGAAAUGUCAUGUGGAUGAGAACGAGAGGCAGAAUGGGGCUGCCAACCACGUGGAAAAAAUUGAGCUUCCAAACAGCACCAGCACAGAUGUUGAAAUGACACCAUCCAGUGAUGCUUCAGAACCUGUACAAAAUGGAAAUCUCUCCCACAACAUUGAAGGUGCAGAAGCCCAGACCGCUGAUGAGGAGGAGGACCAGCCUCUCAGCCUUGCCUGGCCUUCUGAAACCCGCAAGCAAGUCACGUUUCUGAUUGUUUUCCCCAUAGUGUUUCCUCUCUGGAUUACGUUACCUGACGUUCGCAAACCUUCAUCGAGGAAGUUUUUUCCCAUCACGUUCUUUGGCUCCAUUACCUGGAUUGCAGUAUUCUCUUACUUGAUGGUCUGGUGGGCGCACCAGGUUGGAGAGACAAUUGGCAUCAGUGAAGAGAUUAUGGGCCUGACCAUCUUGGCUGCUGGGACCUCCAUCCCUGAUCUUAUCACCAGUGUCAUAGUGGCCCGGAAGGGGUUAGGGGACAUGGCUGUGUCCAGCUCUGUUGGAAGCAACAUUUUUGACAUCACUGUAGGGCUCCCACUGCCCUGGCUCCUGUACACCGUCAUUCACAGAUUCCAGCCAGUGGCUGUCAGCAGCAAUGGCCUUUUCUGUGCCAUCGUCCUUCUCUUCAUCAUGCUGCUCUUCGUCAUCCUCUCUAUCGCCCUCUGCAAGUGGCGAAUGAACAAAAUCCUGGGCUUCAUCAUGUUUGGCCUCUACUUUGUGUUCCUGGUGGUGAGCGUUCUCCUAGAAGACAGAAUUCUUACAUGCCCCGUCUCCAUCUAGCAGGAAAAGCCAUAUCUUGCACCAGCAGCAUGAAUGGUCCCUCCACACUCUGGGCUCUGGGCUCCUUGACCUCUUGAGAAGAGGCAGCUGGCACACAGCCCUGGGUGCCAAGUGUCCCUCCUUGGUGAAUUUGAGGAGAGAUGGAUUCACACUGGGCCCAUUCACUUCACAGGCUGCUUCCACCCUGCCUACUGAAAUGACUUCAUGUAAAAGACAAAGAGAACCGUCAAUACAGGGCUUCUCCCUAUUCACCACUGACAAGUACACCUCGCUGGUCGGAGGUACAGUCGAUGCAAACAAGGACACAGGCUAUAUAUAUCUAUAAAUACACAUAUUAUAAAUAUACGCACAUGAACACACAAAUCCUGCCUGUUCCUGUACUAUACCUCUCCUUGCAUACCUAUAGAUUAGUACAUACCUGUAAAUAAAGACAAAGAAAAAUUAUAUAUAUAUAUAUAAAAUCAGAUAUAUAUAAAAGUACAAAUGCAUCUUUUCAGGGAUAGCUCUAGUAUAUUUAUAGUACUUAUUUGAAGAGGGGCAUCAACUUGCAGUCUGGGCUUUACCUCUUAAGUACAAGAGGUGAACUAAUGGAACCAACAAGACAAAGGUAGCAUUGCUGUGACCUUCAGCCUACCUUGGACUUGCUGUGAUCCUGCCUAGUAAGGUAGAUGGUUUAGGGAAAUAGCUUGCAGGGAGGAGGGCUUAGUGGAGAAGGUCUGUAGGGGCCCUGAGUUGAGCCUUCCAAAACAUUCCUACAAGCCAAACAGAGAGACUAUCUGCCCACCUCCACCAGAGUACCCUGACCAAGAAACUCAGGGUACUUAGGACAGAAAGAGGUAAAAACCCAGGCUGGGUGGCUUGGUUUGGGGAAGUGGGGAGGUAACCAGGGUUGGGUUGUUUUGUUUUGUUCUUAUAUUGUCCCAGCAUGCAAGUAGAAAAUAUGACUACAAACCAAAUUAGUGCUUUUUCUAGGACAGCAAGACUAUAUAAACUGAACCUGUAUUUUUCCAGCGCAUGUCCCAUUAUCAUCAAAAGAAGAGGGGUAAGUUUAGCUGUGAUUGUCAUGUAGAUAUAUUUUGAUGCUAAGGGCUGCCAAGAGAGCCUAGAUGUGCAAUAAGAAGUCAUCCAGUAAAGGUGCUUAGUGGGCCUUGCCACCUAAUGGGAUGUAAGGGCAUAGUUCUUUAAAACGUUUUCCAGUGUAGUCAUAAAGGGCUUUAGUGUCUGAAGAAAUCAUUAUUCCCAAUAGCACUAACUUAACUCUGAUCAGCACUGCUUGGGUUGAGGCAACUUAGCGAUGCUUGGAAAGGCAUUUGCACACUCAGUGCACCCCAGGAAGGUUUCUGAGUGCCAGGUCGAGUGGUACCAGGACCAGGCUUUGGUUAAAGUUCUUGUAACAUCUAUGUCUCUUCUUCCAUCAAGACCUUAUCUGGGAUUCUGUCUAAGUUUUAGAGUACACGGUAUUUGACAGCUUCCUUAUACUGGUUUCAAGCUAUUCACUCCAACAAUUUGAUUUCUUGAUUUUGCUCAACAUUACAUUGAAUGCAUGAAAUUAAAAUAUUCCACGCCCCCAAGUUCUGUAUGACACCUUGUGUGUUUUCUCAGAUCUAUGUCAGUCGAAAAUAAAGCCAGCAAGGGGGAAAAAAUAGGCAAACUGAAUCAAUGGAAAACUAUGUAGAGCACUUUUCUUUUCUCCAAGUCAUGCUUUCCUUAAAAUCAGUUGAAAAAUUGAAUCAAGGAUGGUUCAUUAUUCUGUACCCAUCCUACGUCUAAGUUGGUACAUAUGGCAUAUGGGAAAUUUCACCAUAUGUGUUCCUAUCUCCAAUCUAUUCUGUCAUUGACGCCUGCUAUGAUUUUGUUGUGAGCACAUACCUCUUAACAUAAGAGGACAGGAUGCAGAACUCACAGCAGAAUAAGAGGAAAGGUAACCUGACAGCCCCAGAUCAAGCUCAGUAUUCCUUCCAGAAAACCUCAGCUCACCCCACAGAGCAUGGCAAUAACAGGAAAUGCCCAUCAUUCCUCUUCACCCAGAAGUAAAAAGCACUUCAAACCCGAGGCCCCCUGGGAAAACAAGAAAUCAAGAUGGCUGCCAGUCGGAGGCUGGCUUUCAAGUCUCUCCAACUCGGCAGAUUGGGGUCUUCAGAUGUGGGACAAUGCCUUCCAAGACAUUGAAACACCAUCCAAUAGAGGCGCUGAGUGGAACCUGCCACCUAAUGGGAAUGAAUCUCAUUCAUCAAGGUCAGGACUUUGUACUGGGGCAAGAAUUUGUCCUGCUUCCUUAGAGAGUGAAAGAAUGAGGAAGUGAACUUUACGUUUAAAAACUCCAGUUGUUUUCCCUGUGUAUUUCUUGAAGGGCAACCAAGUUGGUUAUUGUGUGAAUUUUAUAUUAUUGACUGGUGCGUUGUUUGAAAUAAGGUUUAAAUAGGUGACUGACUCAACUGCAAACAGACCAUGUAAAACAGAAGUUGAAGGAGACCUGAUGCCGCCCUCUUCUUAUUCCUGAUCCUCCCUCUGCCUCCUCACUCCCUCCCAUUUAUUCCCAGCUUACAGUGAAGGCUGAUCAAAGCAGCUAUGGUGCCCUUUGCUUGUCUCGGAGCUCCACUUCACAGGAAGUGUUGUGGUCUUUCAUGUGAAGUUGCAUUUGAGAAGACAAAAUUUCCAAGCCCCGUUCCCACAUCAGUCAUGUGCACUGAGCCUGACCUACAACAGCACUGCUCCCUCACUGGAUGGGACACAAGUGAUUCCACAGCCUGCCCUUGCUUUCCCUUCAUUUCUGUGUCUGUAAGUGGUUAUGUGUUGAGCCAGGGUAAAUUCAGAGAGAUGUGUACAGAGUUCAACAAUGGGUCUUUAAACCAUUCAAAUCAUUGGCAUAAUUAUAAGAACUUUCCACACCGUGGUUUCCAAAACAGGUCAUCUCUAACUCGUUUCCUGCAUGCCUGUGUAUAUACAUAUAUAAAUAUAUACAUAUAUAUAUAUAUACAUAUAUAUAUAUAUAUAUAUAUCUUUAUACCAGAUCUAUAUGUACACAUAUAAUAUGACUUACAUCAUCACCCUCUGACCCUAUCACAUUCAGGAUUCUAAAGCAGGGAGCAUCAAGUUUGCCAAAGUCAAGGAAAAGGAAAGUCAUGCACACAAACCAAAGGGAACAUUUCUUCCUGAUUUCAUAAGGUUGUUUGUUCCAUGCACAUAUAUUUACAAAUAUACACAUAUGUACCCAUAUUUUCCCACCCUAAGAAUAUCAAUUUAUAGCCUUAAGGAAAUCGGUCAGCCAUAUCCCUAAUGCUGAUAUAGAGGCAAAGAAUACACAACAGAAAAUACAAAGCAAAAAUUUAGACUGCAGAUACUCUCUUUGCUUCUCUGGAGCAGGGUAUAAAAGAUAUCAACAAUUCAAGAGCCAACAUUGUACUAAUCAAUCUAAAAUAAAUGAGUUGCACGCAAAUGAUUUCAUUUAUUCACAGCAAACCGAGCAGGUCUUGCUUGCUGUCACCGCCUACCCUCCCCCAUACUUCCAAGGCAGCAGAGCAGCUUGGCUCAAACUGACAAUUCCCAAAUAGAAACUCCUAAAUUGCAUCUGAGAAUGCCCAUGCCAACUCCAGCUGCCCUCUGCACCUGACCAGAUCCUGAUGAACUGAAGCUGAAGAUCAGAUGGUGUUUAUGCAGCUUCCCAGGACCUAAACUGAGUCAGGCAGUGACAGAGCAAUGAUAUAUGCAGGGACUAAGGGAUAGGGUUGUUUAUACCCUCGGCAGAUGCAGCAGAAUGUCCUAAAGCCUUGCCCAGAAGAUUAUAAAAAGAGGCGGAGACUGUUUUAUAUUCAGGAAAAAUGCUUUGUAAGGCUUCUAACAGGUGUCACCUGACAAGGGCCAUCAUAAUUUAUUUUAUAGGGAAGACAUGAAUCAGGUGGUUUGGAGCCCUUUCAGCAAAACGCAGCUGCCUCGCUGAUUAGACAUUUGACAAUGUUAAUGUACAUCCAUUCCUGGGCAGGGAGAGAGUUGGCAAACUCCCCACCACUGCACAUAGCUUUUAAAGGCCUCUGGAACAGUGAGAGAAGAGAUGAGCUACAAAGGGAGCCCACCCCCAGACCACUUUAACAAAAAGUUGACCAAAGAAAAGACACCUGGUAGAGUGGCUGGCCAGAUAGAGCUGAAGAAGAUGGAAGUUGCAUUAAAUGCUCUGCAGAAAUUACUGCGUUGGACUAUCUAACAUGGGUCUGAUGGCAGGCAUUUCAGAACAUGGCAGUGUGCUUUCCUCCCCACAUCUACCAAACACACACCCACACCCCCACACACACGCGAGAUUAUGUGGAUGCUAUGCCUCCUUGCACCUGGACAGAUUGUUUUUCUGGUAAGUAGGUGGCCCUAUUAUAGGUGGCAGCUGUGUUCCAGAAGAAACAAAGUGAAGCUGUUCUCAGGGUGAUUUCUGGAGAAAACUACUGUCUCCUGAAAGCAUGCAUAGAAGUCAGUGCUCACUCUUGCUAAGCCACAUAUUCCUUAACGAUCCGGCUUAAUAUUUUUAAAAGAUACCUCCUCAACCCCUAUACCUGUCUCAACAAUACUGUCUUCAAUUAUUAGGUAAGGCCUUGUCAUUAAGAGAGGGGUAGGAGAAAAAAUAGAAUAAUAAGGAAAGGGAAGAAAGGAGAUAUUAAUUUCCUAGGAUUCCAAGAAAACAAGUGUCACGUGGAAAUAUAUCCCUAUGUAGUUUAAAACAGUAACAAAUAUCAGGCUAUGUUUAGCCAAUUACAAGAGCCCAUAUACAGUUUUAGAUUUUUUUAAAAAAUAAUCUCAGGAAGACCUUGGGUAAGAAAAGUAACCCUGCCCUAUUCCACCUUCUAUUUACUGUUAGCUCCCUGACUCUGCCUCUGCCUCUGUCUUUGCGUUUCAUUUUUAAUCUCAGAGCUUCAUAUUUUUUAAAUAUAUAGCAAACAAGAAAAGCAAUAAGGGAACUACUCACAGCCAGCUCAACUCUAUUACUUAUGAUUACACCAUGGCAAUAUUCCUUUUUCACCAGGAGCUUUGGACCUGCGCAGGUUGUGGCAUGUAAUCACCCGGAGCAUGUAGUCGUCUGUAGAAAUCACAGGCACACUCAUGUUUGCUCUGGAAGGAAUCUGUUUUCCACAAUGACUCCCCCCAGCUAAUGUACACACUGGCAUUUUGCAUGCCUUCCUCACACAUGGGGCACCAGCCUUGCUCAGAACCACCCAAACUCCACAGAGGCCCUUAAUAUGGCUAGGGACAGAUUUCUUAAGAAAGAGUAAGAAGCAGCUACAAAGGACAAGCAAAUCCACAAGUCAGGCAGCAUUCGAGAGGCAAAAAUGACCCUGCAAUUACGACAGGCUAGGCAACUGUUUUCAAAUUAGCGUACGAACAGUGAGGGACUGUGUAGAGCACCAUAUUAUCUAAGCCAAAGCACUUCUACCAGAUCAUUCAUUGACAGACUGGAAAACCUAAUAAAAUCUUUAAAAACAGACAAAUAUCUAAGUCUGAAAGAAUGCCAUGGAGUUUGCCUAGGCUUCCACCAAAGAUUUAAUUCCAUUAAGAGGGUUUGUCUAGCCUAUCACGCUAAUCCAAAGGACAGUCCUCUUACGGGGGAGAUCCCAGCAUAGAUGCUGGUGUGACCCAGCUCAAUGAUUAACAACCAUCAGCAUCAAGAAAAGCCUCCCUCCAAGUUAACCCAAACCCAUCCACUUAAUGACUUAACUUUUUUUUUUUUUUUUUUUUUUUUUGGCAAAAAGUAACUGCAUCUGGGCACUCUUCACUCUUUGCCCCAUAGUUGGAAGUUACCGCUAUGUGACUCUUUACCUAUUUUCAAUUAAAAUUAUCUUUAGAUUUUUAUUUGAGUCUUUAACCCUCUUAAUAAUUUUUAUAGUUCCUCUCUACUAAGCCUUUUUAAGUUCUUUAUAUUGUUCUUAAAUGAUGGAACCUUAUGACUAAUGAUAAUCACUGUCUGAACAGUGUUGAACUAUACUGGGUGCAGCAUGACCAUGAAGCUCUGGUGAAGUCAAGGUCACAAACUGCUUUUAAGGUCAUUAGGUCAUAAUCUCAGACUCACAAAGAACUCAAAAUUGGGGAGACACCACUUUAGAUUACUCCAAAACUCUGGGCCUGUACUUACCCACUAAUUUAUCAAGAGGAAUCAAUAUUUUUAUUUUAAAUAUGAAACUGGGAUAAAUGAUUGGAUCUCCACUUAUUAACCAGUACUGCAGUGUGUUUAUAUCCUUUUGUGUGGUAGGUUGGAUAGGAUUUGUAAAGCUACUGAUUGAUCUCAUGGGCCAGGGUUCACCAAAAGGAUGGGAAUUUGUUUCUGCAUUCUUACAUAUUGGGUUGCAUAUUCCUUCAUAAUGGAUCCAUAAGUAACUAAGGCCUUGGAGACUAACAGUUCUCCAAAAUACUCAGCUAACCAAAAGAAAAUACUAAUUUUUAAAAUCAUGUCAUAAAAAACAGAAAAGUAAAAAAAGUCUGAAAUCCUGAAUAAAAUUAUUUUAAGGAUGAAAUUACAUGCAUAAAUUAAGGGUAGAUAACUUCUUGCCAUUUAAUUAAACAAAUCCCCAAUUCUUAUCAGAAUAAAACUGAAGGACAAUGGAUGCCUUUUGGGUUUUUUAAUUUUUUAAUAUUGCACUUUAUAGUACUUCAUAAGAGACAACUGUCUUAAUUAAAGCCAUAAAAUACCAAUAAUACAUAUAUUCAGGGCUUCUGAAUAUAGUCAAUCAAUAAGCAGUCCAUGAGUCAUUCCUGUUUUGUAUUGUUUAUUGUAAAUUGGAGUUUAUCUGUUCUAUUUUUUAUUAACUACAAUUAUUGUUCUAGGCAAUCCUAAUCUACUUAUACAUUUUAGAUGUGUGCUUUAAUAAAACUGUUUGAAAAUCAAAGAAAUUAUUCAUUUCACAAAAGCAGUCUUCGUUUUCAAAAUAGCUUAUUACAGUUUCUUUAGCAAGUUCUAAUACUACAUGGAAAUUAUUUUAAAAUUGUAGAUUUUUUUCAGGAAUCCAUUUUGUUAUAUAAAGCAAAGUUCACCCAUAUGGAAAAUGAAAUAGAUAAUUAGCAAACAUAUACCUGGGAAAUGUAGGAUGUGUUUGAGCUUUUAUAUAAAUAUAGGAUGGGUCUAAGAAGUUCCCUUAUAAAAAUGGGAAAUAGAGGUAUACAAUUUAUCAAUAAUUCCUUAUGCCUAAAUUACUAACCUUCCUUGGGAGGACAUGUAAAGCAGCAGAUUUCAUAAUGCUUUGGUGGUUAUUUUCCUCCUCUCCGCUAAAAUACACAAUUUCUAACCUAGUAUGGUACACUGUUUACACACACAUAUAUAAAGAUGUCCCCACAACUAAAAACUUUAAUGUUUCAACUUCAUCACAAAUUUUUAUAUAAUUUUUUUUUUAACAGACAGGGUCUUGCUCUGUCACCCAGGCUAGAGUGCAGUGGUGCAAUCAUAGCUCAGUGUAGCCUCAAACACCUGGACUCAAGCGAUCCUCCCACUUCAGCCUCUUGAGUAGCUGGGACCUCAGGCACAUGCCACCAUGCCUGGCUAAUUUUGUUGUUGUUGUUAAGAGAUGGAGUCUCACUAUGUUACCCAGGCUGGUCUCAAACUCCUGGGCUCAAGAGAUCCUCCUGCUUUGGCCUCCCAAAGUGCUGGGAUUAAAGGAAUGAGCCACCAUACCCAGCCCUUUUAUGUAAUUUGAGUAAAAGUAAUUACUAAAAAGCACUUAAUAGUCUAGAAAUCCACCAGAACUGGGUACCUAAAUUGUCCAUAUAGAGUAAACAUGGGUACUAAACUGGACAACCCCAUCAAUUUUAUGCUUAAGUGGCCAAAUUGCCCUAAAGAAAGGGUAUCUGAACCAAGGGCCAGUGAUAUUCCUCUGUUAGAGGCUGUUUUGUGGUCUGAAGAGUUUCUCUAAAGGGCUGAGACUCUAUUCGGAAGAGGGAGCCUCAGUUACUGAAUUGCGCUAUUGAACCCUGAACACAAAGUACACAUAUAUACCCUGCAUCUAGCCUUGAUAUUUCUUCUGCUCAAGUCAAAAAACUCCGGAAGCAACAGCUUCCACCAUCAAGCAAUCCACAUACUUAAAAAGCCAUCAAAGCUAAGAAUAGCAAAAGCUACCUUCCUGAUUCAGUGAAGUUGCUGCUAGCACUAAAAGCAAGAGAAAUUAUACUUUUGUUCUUCAGAUACGGUUAAAACAAAGAAAAUGUUGUCAACGUUGACGCCAACAUAGACAUUUGCUCUAUAACAUAUAAACUGUCUUUUAGACAGGUUAUGUUAAAAAUAUCAGAAUGCCAUUUUUGUAAAGGAUCUUUUUUAGGAUAGACGUGGUCUCAUGCUUCCUUUGUUCGCCUCCGUUUUAAAGGAGCAUUGUAACCCCUAUCCUCAUCCCUACAAAAAUCCAGUGGAUGCACUUCCAAAUUACUUCUGUCAUUUUGUAUGUGUUGUGUUUAUUAUGCGUAAUUUUCACUGGAUGAUGAGAUACAUGGUGAUACUAUGUCAGUUUAUUCUCUGUGAAUAUGUCUGUACAUAGACAGGAAGCUCUACUUAUUUGUACAUAGGCUGUCUGAAGUAUGUACUUCUGUCACAUGGACUUCAUUCUGAUAAAGGGUGUUUCUUCUUGUUUCACUGUCCAUACCUUUGUGCUUCUACUACUGAUAAUCAAUUCAUAGAAUAUCACUUUAUGUAACUAAGUCUCCUCAGUGUGAAAAAUAAUAGUAAUAAAAUUAUUGACUCAAAGAA